AGUGGUUGCUAUCCCUGCCUGGCAGGACCAUCAGCAGCAGGUUAGAGAGCAAAUGUUCAUGCAGAUGAGGAGCUUCCUCAGGAAUCUGUGGUCUGUAGAUGCCCUCAAGGGUCAACAUGUGCUUUCUUUGCUAAGAUUUGGGGAUUUCUGACUUCCUGCCAGCUUGGUACGGCAACAAGGUGAUUCUGGCUAGAGUCUCAGUAGGGCUGCCACCUCUCAGCAUGGUGCCAGGAGAGGGAGCCCUGGAGUCAUCAGCUCUGGACAGGCCUGGAGGUGGCCUUUCAAGUCCUCUGACCUGCGCAUCCUGUGUGUUGCAAGUGAAGGAUCUGACACUAGCCUUCAUUUUCACUCAGUCAUCAAGCUUUCUCCAUCUCCACUGGGUAUAGGGUUUGGACACUCAGAAAGAAUUCUAGAAUCCAGUGAUAGAUCCCAGAACCAGAGACAUCUAGAGAAUCCUAGAAAGGAAUUCUAGCAUCCAGCAAUUAGGCUUUUGAAUCCAGGUUCAACAGUAAAACAAUGGGGAGUGGAAUGGAGUUAGGACUACUGAAGACGAUGAUUAUCAUGUGAUGAGCACCUAAGCUGAACUGGACACUGUGCUGAGCACUUUCCAGCCACUAUCUCACUCAAAUGAGUUCAGGACCAGCGUGAGGAGGCUCCUGGCAGUUGCCCACAGGACCAGCGUGAGGAGGCUCCUGGCAGUUGGGCUGUUCCGGGCCGGCGGCAGGAGGGAGCUUGAUGCGUGCCUGGCGUGCGCAGGCCGAUGCCGCCGGCAGAAAAGAGCGAGGGGCCACCGGUCCCGGCGCCCGCGGAACGCGCCCGGGGCCGGGUGCCCGGCCUGCCGUCGCCGGCGCUGUGCUGCGCCUGCGGUCUGUGCGCGCUGCUGGCGGGCGUGAACGUGACGCUGGCAGGCGCCUUCGCCUCCUUCUUGCCCGAGCACAACGCGCUGCUCGUCGUGGGGCUGGCGCUGCUGGUGCUGGCGCUCGGCUUCUUCGCGGCCUGCUGCGUGUGUAGCCGCCGGGGCCUCGCGCCCCGUGGGCGCUCGGCGGCCGCGGCGGGCCCGGGCCAGGGUGGCGGCCGCGCCGGGCCCGUGGCGCUGGAGAUGGAGAGCAGCGAGCCCACGGCACAGGACACCACGGCCGUGCAGCUCAGCCCUGCCGUCUCCGCCGCGUCCUCCGGCUGCUCCAGCCCCGGCCCCAGCCCCCUCGCCCUGGAGGCCCCGGCGCCCGCGGCCGUCUGCGCGCUGCGCUCGGAAGGAGUCCAGCUCAACCCACCCCGGGCGCGCGCCGCCCCCUAGCGGACCAGGGCCCCGCCGUGACUCCGCUGUCCGGGUUCAUUCCCCUUCCUUCAGUGCCAUUUAAGGGGGGAAAAGAAAGAAAAGAAAAAGAAAAAAGAAAACCUUUUCUUCCUUCCUUCCUUUCUUUUUUACAAGGGUCUGGUGCUGGGCUCAGGUGGCCUCAUCUUUUCCAUCUCCCAAACUCCUGGGUAGAAUGUGGUGAUGGUGUCAGGGGUCACACCCCAAAGAAGGGAGCAGCAGAGCCUUGGCCCCUUAGACAGGGUCUCUGGUCUCUAGUAAACCUUACCCAUCCAGCUUGCUGAAAGUAGGCCCCUGGACCCUGGAACCCUGACACUGCCACCUCCCCCUGGCAUUUGGGCACUGUGAACCAAGGAGCACCCACCCUGAAGGGGCUAACCACCAGCAGUCCCCCCAGUGAGGUGGGAGGAAGAGAGGGAGAAGGGUUGAAUGUCAGCCUGGGCUGUCUCUGUCCUUGCACACACCGUGAAAGGCUUCCAGUCCCCUCUCCUGCCCCUCCCCACCUUCCUUGUUUCUACCCCAACAUGACCUUUGGGAUUCAUUUGGCUGAGAAGCCGUGGCUCUGACUUGGGCCAGGAUGGUCCCUAGAAUUAGGGCCGGGGUGAGCACUCCCCACCCUUUCUGUCUGACUAAGAGCAAGAGUAGCUGAGACUGGGGCCCUGACAGAGGUGAGUGGUGAGGGAGCUUCUGCAGCCCUGAAAGUCCUAGUGUGACUUUCACUGCCAGCAAUGCUGGCCCCCACCCACCCUGACUGUGGCACACCAUGCAUUCCUGCAGUGCCUUACUCCUCAAUAAAGCACCUUUGGAGUC